AACCUUCUUCAGUGAGGAGGUUAUACCCGGAGGUCUCGACGCUCGCUCGUGCUGCUCGUGUUGCCGCUGGGUACGUUUGCUGCCAGUGCUGAUCCAGCCGGAGGCGAAGAGAAGCACUUUGGGGGCAAAAGUCUCUCUUCAGAAUCUUCUGAUGGCAUGCUAACAAUUGUAGAUGGCAACUGUGUUGGAAACUAGGGGAUCCCAUCUGAGUUGGUCAAAGUCUGCCAAAAAGAAAAAAGAAAACCAAUAUUUAAGAGAAGAGAAAAAUGAAGACGGGACAUUUUGAAAUAGUCACCAUGCUGCUGGCAACCAUGAUUCUAGUGGACAUUUUCCAGGUGAAGGCUGAAGUGUUAGACAUGGCAGAUAAUGCAUUUGAUGAUGAAUACCUGAAAUGUACGGACAGGAUGGAAAUUAAAUACGUUCCCCAACUGCUAAAGGAGGAAAAAGCAAGCCACCAGCAAUUAGAUACUGUGUGGGAAAAUGCAAAAGCCAAAUGGGCAGCCCGAAAGACUCAAAUCUUUCUCCCUAUGAAUUUUAAGGAUAACCAUGGAAUAGCCCUGAUGGCAUAUAUUUCCGAAGCUCAAGAGCAAACUCCCUUUUACCAUCUGUUCAGUGAAGCUGUGAAGAUGGCUGGCCAAUCUCGAGAAGAUUAUAUCUAUGGCUUCCAGUUCAAAGCUUUCCACUUUUACCUCACAAGAGCCCUGCAGUUGCUGAGAAAACCUUGUGAGGCCAGUUCCAAAACUGUGGUAUAUAGAACAAGCCAGGGCACUUCAUUUACAUUUGGAGGGCUAAACCAAGCCAGGUUUGGCCAUUUUACCUUGGCAUAUUCAGCCAAACCUCAGGCUGCUAAUGACCAGCUCACUGUGUUAUCCAUCUACACAUGCCUUGGAGUUGACAUUGAAAAUUUUCUUGAUAAAGAAAGUGAAAGAAUUACUUUAAUACCUCUGAAUGAGGUUUUUCAAGUGUCACAGGAGGGGGCUGGCAAUAACCUUAUCCUUCAAAGCAUAAACAAGACCUGCAGCCAUUAUGAGUGUGCAUUUCUAGGUGGACUAAAAACCGAAAACUGUAUUGAGAACCUAGAAUAUUUUCAACCCAUCUAUGUCUACAACCCUGGUGAGAAAAACCAGAAGCUUGAAGACCAUAGUGAGAAAAACUGGAAGCUUGAAGACCAUGGUGAGAAAAACCAGAAGCUUGAAGACCAUGGUGUGAAAAUCCUUGAACCCACCCAAAUACCUGGAAUGAAAAUUCCAGAACCUUUUCCACUACCUGGAAUAAAAAUGAUACAACUGAAUGAAAAACCUGGUAAUAUAUUCUUUAUUGGGGGUGGAGGCACCAUGGAUUCUAAGUCCUUUACCAUAAUCAUUCAGUUAGUUCAGUCUUAUGGGGUCUGGGGAAGACAUCUGGGCUGUACACUUUCCGAUAUCCCAGUCUGCAAGCCAGACAGGGAAAGUGUUGAGAAUUUCUUUCAGUGUGAGCAGCAGGCUGCUAUUACGGUUCUCUGGGCCAAACAUCAAAAAAGGCACUUGAUCUUAAACUGGAACAGUUGGCUUCCAGCUGGGCCUGUCUAUUCCAGAAUGAGGCAGGCUUCUCAGGGUGAAGGAAUCUGUAGACAUAGAAAUAGCAUCAUCCAAGAACUGUGAAUGAGGACUGUGCAGCAUGCCAAUACUGGGACCAGCCAUUCUGUGUGCUCCUCACCACACUCUACAAUCGUCCAGUAGGCCACUAGAUUUUGUUGGGACUACAGUGUAUUGUGCCCUCUCCUGGAAAGCUAUGUGUAGCUUUUUAAAAGGUGAUGUGAAAACAGUACACAGGAGCUCAUUUAAUCCAAUACGAUAAAUAUUAUUGACACUUCAGAGAUGAGAACAUGGAACAUAAGAAGGCUAACAAAUUUAUAAUAGGCUAGAGACAACCAGGACUCAAACUUUUCAAGCUUUGUUCACUUUGUGCUACACUUGUCUUCCAAACAGAUUUAGUUAUCCACUUCUAUCCUGGGCACCUAGAAUUGGUAUUUGGCUUCAAAGCUGUUAAAAUAUGGUAAUAUCAUAAUAUUUCUAUGCUAGGCACACACUUGGUAGUACAGAUGGUCUCCAAGUUACAAUGGUCAGUCUGUAAGAAACACGAAAAGGUGGCUUGCCAGUUAGGACAGAUUUAUUUUAGAGAAAACAAACUUGAGAGGCGCCUUCUGGCCGAGUUAGGUUAGAGGCCCACUUUUUUACAGACUAAGAGUUUUUAAGGAUUUAGGGUGGGAGAGUUUAUCAGCGGCUUGGACUGCUUCUGUGUCUCUUUGUUGUGCUUAUCUGGGAGAGAGCGUUGUGUGUCUGUUCCCAUACAUCAUUCUGCAGCUGCAGGCAUAUUCCCCAAGUCUGCUUUUAGCUUCCCUAACUUAGUGCACCUGAAGAGAAAGGAAUGUGCUUAUUAAGGCCCACUGUUUUACUGGGGCCCACUGUAUGAGGGCGAAGUUUGGGAGUUACUCAAGAGACUUCCCCCCCACCUCCCUUUGUGCCCGAGCUGUUUUAUCUGUGUUUUACUGUUUGCUCCUUCUGGCUGCUUGUAGUUAGAAGAGGUGAUUUCCUUGAAAUGCAUGAGGCUAGAAAGGGAGCUCGAAUUUAAAGUGGUGGUGUUUGUCCAAGAUGACGGUGCUCCUGCUCUAUCAGGUUCAACUUGGGAUUUUUUGAUUUUGCAAUGGUCUGAAAGCCAUACACAUUCAGUAAAAACCAUACUUCAAGUACCCAUACCGUUCUCUUUUUCACUUUCUGUACAAUAUUCAAUAGAUUACAUGAGACAUUCAAUAUUUUAUUAUAAAAUAAGCUUUAUCUUAGCUGAUUUCGCCCAACUGCAGGCUCAUGUAAGUGUUCUGAGCACGUUUAAGGUAGGCUAGGUUAAGCCAUGAUGUUCUGUAGGUUGGGUGAGUUAAAUGCAUUUUUGACUUAUGGUAUUUUCAGCUUACAUUGGAUUUAUUGAGACACAACCCCAUCAUAAGUCGAGAAGCAUCUGUAUAGCAUAGUAAUUCAGAGCAAAUUUGAAAUUAGAUAUUUCUAGCACCAGUUACCCCCGUGAUUUUAUGCAUGGCAUUCCUCAAAACAUUUCAUAAAUGUUUUAAGGAAUAUCUGUGAAAUAUGGAUAAUUAUACCUGGCUAAUAAGACUAAGAAGUAAAGGUGACAGUGUACAUAAAGCAUUUGCACAAUGCAUGGCACAUAGUGAACACUCAAUAGUAGGUAUUAAUGUACUUGGGAAUCUAAGUUCAAUAUGUAGAAAAUACUUUUUGUGAAUAAAAUUUUAACUUUUAUUUUUAUGUAAACACAUAUUGAUGGGAAAAAAAAUUCAAAGAGCACAGAUGAGAACAAAUUAAACCCUUCCCCUAACCCCACACAUACCCGUAAACCUAUUACCCUGCCCCUCAGACCCACUCACAGAGAUAACCAAGUUUGCUUAAUUUUUAAUCAGAUCUUUCUUUUCUGGAUAAACAGAUAUACAAUAUAACUAACUCAAAAUCU